GGAGAGCCGCCUGCGCAUGUCAGGGCUGACAGCACACACGGCCUGGGGGCCUAGAGAAGGGUUGCUGAUCACCUGCCACCCAGGGUCGGGGCCCCGCACCAUCCGGGGGCGAGCUCCCGGGAAGGGGCUCCGCCUCUACACCCACCCCCCAACCUCUGACAUCGCCGGCCGAACGGGAGCUGCCGCUUCCUUCCCGGCCCCGCUGCACCUCCCCAGGGAGCCGAGGGCGGGCGUGGACGGGACCGACGUGGAACGCAUUCUGUAGCCCAGACGGGCGGCCCCGGCGGCUUCGGGAGUGGGGUCACGCCCAGCUGGAGAAGCAGUUAGGGCGGACGAAGCAGGAGCCGCGGGGCUGGGAGGAUUCCAGUCGGAACGCAACCGAUCCUGGGGAGGCGAGAGGUGAAUCAACCUGGACCCUUCCACAGCCUGGCUGCUAGGCCAGCAGUGCGACUCCCUUCCGAGCUGAGCUUACCCUGGGCGCAAACGAGCGAGGCAGGGGCGCGAGUGGAAGCUGGAGUUCCGGGGUGGGCGGGGAGGCGACUGUCCGUGGUGCUGAGCGCCGGCGAGAGCGGGCGCGGAGCGGCUGAUCGGCUCCCUCGAACUGGGGAGGUCCAGUGGGGUCGCUUAGGGCCCAAAGCCCCCACCCGGCUCCAAAAGCUCCCAGGGCCUCCCCAGGCACCGGUGCUCGGCCCUUCCUUCGGUCAGAAAGUCGCCCCCUGGGGGCAGUUCGUCCCAAAGGGUUUCCUCGAAAGAAUCUGAGAGGGCGCAGUCCUUGACCGAGGGAAUCUCUCUGUGUAGCCUUGGAAGCCGCCAGCCCCAGAAGAUGCCUGCCUUCAAUAGAUUGUUUCCCCUGGCUUCUCUCGUGCUUAUCUACUGGGUCAGUGUCUGCUUCCCUGUGUGUGUGGAAGUGCCCUCGGAGACGGAGGCCGUGCAGGGCAACCCCAUGAAGCUGCGCUGCAUCUCCUGCAUGAAGAGAGAGGAGGUGGAGGCCACCACGGUGGUGGAAUGGUUCUACAGGCCCGAGGGCGGUAAAGAUUUCCUUAUUUACGAGUAUCGGAAUGGCCACCAGGAGGUGGAGAGCCCCUUUCAGGGGCGCCUGCAGUGGAAUGGCAGCAAGGACCUGCAGGACGUGUCCAUCACUGUGCUCAACGUCACUCUGAACGACUCUGGCCUCUACACCUGCAAUGUGUCCCGGGAGUUUGAGUUUGAGGCGCAUCGGCCCUUUGUGAAGACGACGCGGCUGAUCCCCCUAAGAGUCACCGAGGAGGCUGGAGAGGACUUCACCUCUGUGGUCUCAGAAAUCAUGAUGUACAUCCUUCUGGUCUUCCUCACCUUGUGGCUGCUCAUCGAGAUGAUAUAUUGCUACAGAAAGGUCUCAAAAGCCGAAGAGGCAGCCCAAGAAAACGCGUCUGACUACCUUGCCAUCCCAUCUGAGAACAAGGAGAACUCUGCGGUACCAGUGGAGGAAUAGAACAGGAGCAGUGUGACAUGAGGUGGCCUGAACACCUGAGGGACUGGACAUCCCAUGUUCAGCAAUGUCAAUGGCAUCAGGAGGGCGCCCCAAGGGCCCCAUCGCUUCCCUUCAUGCAUCCAUUGUUCUGUUCAUUCAUUCAUCCAUACAUCCACCUGCCUCUGAGCUUUCACCUCUGACUCCCUAACUCCAUCAGACCUCUACGCACCAUAAGACUCUGCCAGAACUGAGAAGCCAACAUUUCUACAUAGACUCAACCUCACCCUCUCCUAGUUUUCCAACAAGACACUCCAAAGCCAACUGGAUUUCUCCCCUGUGCUCCAAAUGACUUUGUACAAGUGCUGGAGUUAGCACCUCCCUCUGCCCUUAACUGGCUGGAACUGGUUCAUUCUCCAUUACUGCAAGAGAAUGGAAGUCUUAAUAGAAGGAAGCAGGAGUGAUUAGUUCGGGUUAAAGCAAAAGUGUGUCAUGAACUUGGAUUCCCUGAAGUCAGUUUUGUCAGGUUCAUGGCCCACUUUGCUACAGCAUCAGAGUGAAGCACGCCUGUCUAGGUUCUCCAGUGACAGAAAGAUCCUGAAGCAUGGACUAACAUGCUCUCUGGAGCUUAGUACUCCAGAGCUAGAUCCUGAUGGGUCUCUAAGGUUCCCUCCAAGAAGACAAGGACAGGAGACUUGGGAAGGACCAAUGGUAAUUUAAGUGGCUCUUAAAAAGUCAUGCAACAUGUUUCUGGACACGUUCCUGAUCCUAUUGCGAUAAUGUAUGUGUGCCCUCCCUGUGGGCACACCACCUGGGCAUUAGGACUGAAAUUCCUGAGUUCUUCCUCUCAAAAUUUCUGUGCACCAGUAUUAUUCCUCAUUUUACAUACAGGAGGCAACUAAGACUCAUACAGGGCUCAACUGAAUAAGAGGCUUAAGAGGAUAAACUGGAGCAGAAAUAAGCCUUAGGUGCUGCCCAGUUUACACUUCCUGGGAUGGAUGUUUUUGUUUGUUUUGUUUUUUGUUUUUUUUGUUUGAGAUGGAGUCUCACUCUGUCACCUAGGCUAGAGUGCAGUGGUGUGAUCUCGGCUCACUGCAACCUCUGCCUCUUGGGUUCAAGCAAUUCUCAUGCCUCGGCCUCUCCAGUAGCUGGGAUUACAGGUGUGCACCACCACGCCUGGCUAAAUUUUGUAUUUUUAGUACAGACAGGGUUUGACUAUGUUGGCCAGGCUAGUCUUGAACUCCUGACCUCAAAUGACCCACCCACCUCAGCCUCCCAAAGUGCUGAGAUUACAGGCGUGAGGCACUGCGCCCGGUGGAUAACUUUGUUUCUGAAAAGACUGACAUUGAACUUGUCUAUGGCAAUGCUUCUUUCACAAGCACGGACUGGGCUGAGGUCAACUCUGAUAGAUUCAGAUGACUAGAAAUUGGCCAAAAAAGCAGGGAGAAGAACAUGAGGUAGACUUAAAGAACUUCCUUUAUGUAAAGAUCUGUGACUCUGAAAUAUCCUCCAAAAGGAGAGUGCAUCUGAGACUGAUAUUUAAACUAAGAAAAAUGUUUAGUCUGAGAUGGAUCAUAAGUAAAUGAGCAGUGUGAGAGGGGAGGGAUGGGUAGGUGCUUUCCAAAUACUUCGCCUAUGAAUGCAUAAUUUUCAGAUUUUUUUCCCCUAGAUUUUGAGGGAGCAGAGAAACUGGAAAAAACUUUAGUCAAUAUCUCGUGUUUCAUUUUAAUUAAGUGACAGGUCCAAGUGUGACAUCCUUCAGCACCCAGGGACAAGAGAGGGGAAAGAUGCUUUAUGGAAUGUAAGAAGAUGAAGGUGACUGGGAUUCAGCGAGAGAGAGGUCCCUCAGACCUGGGACCUCCCUUUAUAGGGAAAGACCAUAUUCCAUAGGUUUAGGGCUUUACCUUAAAAGCUCAUUUUUUUCAUUCUUCCAUCCCUAGGAAAGUACUUAAAACCAGACUUUUAAAUUUUUAUUUAUUUAUUAUUAUUUUUUUGAGACAGAUUCUCACUCUGUCUCCCAGGCUAGAGUGCAGUGGUGCAAUCUCAGCUCACUGCAGCCUCAACUGCCCCAGGUUUAAGCAAUCCUCCCACCUCAGCCCCCAGGUAACUGGGACUACAGGCAUGCACCACCAUGCCUGGCUAAUUUUUGUAUUUUAUGUAGAGACAGGGGUCUUGCCAUGUCGCCCAGGCUGAUCUUGAACUCCUGGGCUCAAGCAAUCUGCCAGCCUCAGCCUCUCAAAGUGCUGGGAUUACAGGCCUGAGCAACUGUGCCUGGCCCAAAACCAGACCGUUAACACAUUAAAGAGUCUGAUUUUGUUGAAGAAAAUAUUUGCAAUAAAUUCAAGACUCUUCUUAUUGGUAAUUUUCCACACAAUCCCUCUGAAAUAAGGGAGAGGAUAUAGACCUUUUUAACUUUAUAGUUAGAAAAAUUGGCCUCAGUGUGAAAUUUUUCCAGUCCCAUAGCUCAUGGAUGCCACCAGCUUGCGGUAGUAGCAAGAUGCUUACUACCACACCGUUUUCCUCGGUGGCCCAAUAGCUCGUGUAUCUAAGUUGAACCCGGCAGUAUGCAUGAUUGCCUUUUUCUCUUCUUUUUAAAAAAACCCAACUCAGAUGCUGCUUGCGUGGCUUUUAAUGAAGCUGAAUGGUAUCUAUCACUUAUUUAUCCUUGACAGGUUAUCUUCCCCACUCUUCCUUUUUCUAACUUCUCCAUUCUUCUCAUUCUUGACACUUUCAUUAGAACUAUAUGGUUUACGAAGUAUUUUCACUUAACUAUUUUAUUUCUUCUCUAUAACUGGUCCUGUGAGGUCACAUUACAAAAGAAGAAACUGAGGGUCUCUGAGGUUAAGUAGCUUUACUAAAUUAUAAGGAAACCUAGCUGGUAGGUAGACAGCAAGAAUCCAGGUCUUCUGACUCCUCUUUCAGUUCUCUUUCCACUUAGACCAUAGCUGCUUCCUUUUCUUAUUUUUUAGCUUCCAUCUAACCAUUGCCUAUCUUGCCUGUCCUAAUGUUCUCCAUCUUCUCUCACCCCUAAUCCCACUCACUGCUUCUCUACCACUUUGCUUUUUGGUGGAUGCUAGCAAUGUGCUUUGAGAGUCAGUCCUAUUUUGGUUCUCUUUCUAGUUGGUUUGUACAUCAUUAUUUCUCCUGAAUUGCAAUUAAACUCCUUCCUGGGAGAUUUGAUAAUGACUGUAAAUCAAUAAGGUACUGUGAUCACCAGCCUACUUCCAAUCUCCACCCACCUCCCUGUCUCUUCCCAUAAUCCUACGAAAGACCCAGACUAGAUGUCUGUUUCUCUGGAAGCUUUAUCUGGCAUGAUGUUGCUUAUUAAAGGGCUUAGAAGAGUUCUCAAGGGCUAUUAAUAUCACUUUAGAAACCCCAUCUGUUGUCUUGGUGCUGGAUAUUUCCCAUGUCUGAUCCUCAAUAACACAAUUCACUAAAGGCCAAGCUUGGCUCAAUCUGAUUUUCCCAUUCUUACUACUUCACAGCCAUGAAUGUGAUUGCUCAAUCCAGUUGGCCCUGAGAGCACCUUGCCCUGCUGACCUUCACUGUCACCUCGGUCUUGAAUCAGAGCCCCAACCCAAACACUCCCUGCCUGUCCCUACCCCAGCCUUUAUUCUCACCACUUGUUUAACGGCAUGACCUUUUAGUUUCUCCAUUCCCAGACACCCACACACCCAGACUUCCUUCUGAGUUGCAGGUUUCUCCUUAGAUGUCCAACUAGAAAUAUUACUAGGAAAGUUACUUUUCAAAGCAGGAAUGUGCUGGGAAGUAGGAGACAGCAACUCCCUCCUCUCUCCCCAAAAUUAUUGGAUCAAAAAAGAAAUUCCAUCCAUCUCAGAAUCUGUGAGUCCUCCUCACAUAAAUCUGAGGGAAAAGGCUGUGUCACUGCAUCUUUGCAGGAAGAAAGAGAAGCAAGAGCUAGACACACUUCAGAAUAUAUCUUAGUUUCCCCUUUCCCAGUUUAACAUGAAAAUGAAAAAAGAAAAAAAUGAAAAACAAAAACAAAAGAAGCCUUCCUCUCACCUCAUUUUGUAAAUGAAAAAUCCCUAAUUCAGUGAAUUCACCUAGUCACUGCAAAUGUAUCUGAAUAGUGCUUGGUGUGCUUGCCAGUCUGAUCAUCCACUCAUUCUACUAACAUCUUUUUGCACCCACUCUGUCAAGCUCUAGCCUAGACCUUUAGUGUGCCAUGCAGUCACAGGUCUGAAAAGCAGCAUCAUCCAAACCUUACUUAAUCUCUAAAAUCUCAGCUGGUGGACAGCUCAUGAUUAGUUCAGCCCACUUCCUCCCCCUUAGUUGAGUUUGCAGCAGGACGCAGGAGAUAAGCACUUCCAAGCAAGUCUGAUUUAUAUAUCAAACUCGGUCUCCAUCCCAGGCCAGCUGACCCUCAGAGCCAGCAAUGCUCUGUGCUUCCUCCCUGCGUCACGGCUUGGCAAGAGCUGCCUCUGCUGAGCAGUGUGUGUGAUGGAGACGGAGGCCGCUGAAGGCCGAGUGCUUGCAGGCUUGUGAACUGCCAUCGAACACAAUCCAAACUCUGGAAAUGUUCCUGACCACCUAAGCCCUCAACAACGUAAUGCCUGUAUGUGCUGUUUUUCAGUAAACUCCUUGUUCAUGUCAAUAAAGUAUCCCUGAAAACCA